CUUUACAGGCUCCUCCGCUUCUGUGGCCAGAGGGGACAGCGGAGGAGCCCAGUCCACGAUGGCCCGGUCCCUGGUGUGCCUUGGUGUCAUCAUCUUGCUGUCUGCCUUCUCCGGACCUGGUGUCAGGGGUGGUCCUAUGCCCAAGCUGGCUGACCGGAAGCUGUGUGCGGACCAGGAGUGCAGCCACCCUAUCUCCAUGGCUGUGGCCCUUCAGGACUACAUGGCCCCCGACUGCCGAUUCCUGACCAUUCACCGGGGCCAAGUGGUGUAUGUCUUCUCCAAGCUGAAGGGCCGUGGGCGGCUCUUCUGGGGAGGCAGCGUUCAGGGAGAUUACUAUGGAGAUCUGGCUGCUCGCCUGGGCUAUUUCCCCAGUAGCAUUGUCCGAGAGGACCAGACCCUGAAACCUGGCAAAGUCGAUGUGAAGACAGACAAAUGGGAUUUCUACUGCCAGUGAGCUCAGCCUACCGCUGGCCCUGCCGUUUCCCCUCCUUGGCUUUAUGCAAAUACAAUCAGCCCAGUGCAAA